AUUCACUGGGAACUAACACCCGGCGCCGCUCAGACAUCUCUAUUCCCGCCUCUCCGACCCGGUCUCACUUCGCUCCUGGGCAGCUGCGCGGAGAACUGGGGCUCACCGUCAUGGAUGCUCUAUCAGAAGCAAAUGGCACAUUUGCAUUAAACCUUUUGAAAAAGCUAGGGGAAAACAACUCAAACAACUUAUUUUUUUCCCCAUGAGCAUAUCAUCAGCCUUGGCCAUGGUUUUCAUGGGGGCAAAGGGAAACACUGCAGCUCAGAUGUCUCAGGCACUUUGUUUUAGUAAAAUCGGAGGUGAAGAUGGAGAUAUUCAUCGAGGUUUUCAGUCACUUCUUGUUGCAAUUAACAGAACUGACACUGAAUAUGUGCUUAGAACUGCCAACGGGCUCUUUGGAGAAAAGUCUUAUGAUUUCCUCACAGGUUUUACAGAUUCCUGUGGCAAAUUCUACCAAGCAACGAUAAAACAGCUAGACUUUGUGAAUGAUACAGAGAAGUCCACAACACGUGUAAACUCCUGGGUUGCUGAUAAAACUAAAGGUGAAAAUAUAUUGUUAUUCUAUUUCGAUAAUAUUUUAAACAGUUUUAUAGUCAGUUCUUUACAAAACUGUCAAAUAUAAAAAGGAGUCCUUUUUUCUCUAAACAACUAUGCAAACAUUAAAACCUUUCUUUGGAAAUAUUGCCAACUCGUAGACCUUUUCUCUAGCUUUAGCUUUUCCCUUAUCAAGUAUCUGUGAUGUCUCUCUAGAUGAAAUAAUCUCUUCCAGGUUUUUUUGCUUGUUAAUAUUAGGUAGUUUUUCUUUUCACAAAUAGCGUUAAAAUUUGAAUUUAAAAAUUUCUAGCUGUCUCCCUCACUGGUAUUGCCAUACUGUAUGGUUUACAGGCUUGAAAUGCAACUGCUGUGAUCAGUGAUAAGGGAACACACUGAUGAUUUAGAUUGAACAGGGAGAGUUAUAUUGUUUUCUAGGGCACAGCUAAAAAGACAUUCCAUCAACCCCCUUGCAGCCAGAAAGACCCUGAGCCCUCAGAACUUCACUGACACAACCCAUAUUUUCUUUCCAUAACUGGCCAACUUUUCCCUUUGUACCAAAGCCAGCUACUUAGCUUCAGGGAGAGAAUGAGACUGAAGAUUACAAGGAGACAUCCACAUUAUAUGUGGGCUGAGAGAGGAAAGAGGGAGUAUCAGAGGUUGCCGGGUUUGCUACUCUCAUUCCUCUUCCUCCUCUGCCCAACACUUGGACUUGGAAAGAAGUCUGAAAGGUGGGGAAUAAUCAGCCCAUAUGAUUCUUCCACUGCAGAGAGAGCCUCUGAGUGUUACAGCCAGGAGCAACAGGGUGGCACCCUCUUCUUCAGGGAAACACACACCUCUUUGCACUGCCUUGUGGAUAGUCCAGUCAAGUGGAGUAAGAGGUGGGAGUGGGGAGUGUAAAUGGAGUAACCUCUAAGUAUCCAAGCAGGAGGGUGUUUUUUUUUUUUCUUUCCUGGAAUGAGGAUAAUCAAAUCAUUUCAAUAUGAAUUAUGAAAAUGAAUGAUAAUGGUUUUAUCUGUUAUAGAAAUAUAAUAUAAUCAGACUUUAGCCAUGUAAAUCAUAAAACAUAGAGAUAACAAUAUGCAUAUUGUUCCUAGAGGGUCUUGUGAAAUUUUGUUUGUCAUAUUCUCUUUGAAGAGUUAUCAUUCACUAUUUUAUUUCUGUCUUGUAAAGCCUGAAAGCUCAUGUGCUGCCUUGACAUCUAUGGGCUUCUCAGGGCCUCAGAGGCCUGGCCAUGAAGUCCCCUGCUCUUGUCAGAUAUGUGCACCCUAUUCACCCACUGAGCAGGAAGGCUCUUCCCCCUUCUAAGUUCCCUUACCAGGCAGUCAGCUGUACCCUCCCUGGGUCUCAACGUGGCUCACUUCCCUCCAGCCUGGAAAAUUAUUCAAACAAGCCUGUCACAUCUGGAGGAGCCAGGAAUCGCCUCUUCCUCUUGUUACUGCAAAGCCUGCCUUCCACAGCCCCUACUGGUUCACUCUAUUCCCAAAUGCAACUCUCCUGUGACCCCGCAUGGCAUGUGGUGACCUCCCUCCCUGUGAGCAGUUGUGACUAAUAAACUGCCGCCAAUUUCA